CCGGCUCGGCGAAGCAGGGAAGGGGAGAGAAGCAGGAGUCGGGAGACUGCACAGGCCAGAAAGUCUGCGGAGCGGGCCGCGCCCCUGGCCCGCCCGGGCUCCAAGUCCCGCGUCGCCGCCCUGGCGGGGACGGUGCAGCAGGCGGCGGGAUGCGGCGGGGCGGCAGCCUGAGCGCCCCGGAUGGCCCGCGGCGGGGCGGCCUGCAAGAGCGACGCGCGGCUGCUGCUGGGGCGGGACGCGCUGCGGCCGGCGCCCGCCCUGCUGGCCCCCGCCGUGCUGCUGGGCGCCGCGCUCGGCCUCGGCCUCGGCCUUUGGCUUGGCUGCCGCGCGGGCCGCCAGCGCACGCGACACCAGAAAGACGACACUCAAAAUCUGCUCAAGAAUUUGGAGUCUAAUGCGCAGACCCCCUCGGAAACUGGCUCCCCAUCAAGGAGGAGGAAGAGAGAAGUGCAGAUGUCGAAGGACAAGGAAGCUGUUGAUGAAUGUGAGCCGCCUUCCAACAGCAAUAUCACAGCAUUCGCCCUGAAGGCCAAAGUCAUCUACCCCAUCAAUCAGAAGUUCCGGCCUCUGGCCGAUGGCUCCUCCAACCCGUCUCUGCAUGAAAACUUAAAGCAGGCUGUUUUGCCACACCAGCCGGUAGAGGCCUCUCCUUCCAGCAGUCUGGGGAGCCUGAGCCAGGGUGAGAAGGACGACUGCAGCUCCUCAUCCAGCGUCCACUCGGCCACCAGCGAUGACAGGUUUCUCAGCCGCACCUUCCUCCGGGUGAACGCCUUCCCUGAAGUGCUGGCCUGCGAGAGUGUAGACGUUGACCUGUGUAUCUACAGCCUUCACUUAAAAGACCUGCUGCAUUUGGACACGGCACUGAGGCAGGAAAAGCAUAUGAUGUUUAUUCAGAUUUUUAAAAUGUGCCUCCUUGACCUUCUUCCUAAAAAGAAGUCAGAUGAUGAACUAUACCAGAAGAUCCUUUCAAAACAAGAAAAAGAUUUGGAGGAACUAGAAAAGGGACUUCAGGUCAAACUGUCAAACACAGAAAUGUCGGGGGCUGGUGACUCUGAGUACAUCACCCUGGCUGAUGUGGAAAAGAAGGAGAGAGAAUACUCUGAACAGCUAAUCGAUAAUAUGGAAGCUUUCUGGAAACAGAUGGCAAAUAUCCAGCACUUUCUUGUGGACCAGUUUAAGUGUUCCAGCUCCAAAGCCCGACAGCUGAUGAUGACUCUGACGGAAAGAAUGAUUGCAGCCGAAGGGCUAUUGUGCGAUUCUCAGGAGCUGCAGGCUCUGGACGCCCUGGAGAGGACGAUGGGGCGGGCGCACAUGGCAAAAGUGAUUGAGUUUCUGAAGCUGCAAGUCCAGGAGGAGACCAGGUGCCGGCUGGCUGCCAUCUCCCACGGCCUGGAGCUGCUGGCUGGUGAGGGGAAGCUGUCCGGGCGGCAGAAGGAGGAGCUGCUCACGCAGCAGCACAAGGCCUUCUGGCAGGAGGCAGAGCGCUUCAGCCGGGAGUUUGUCCAGCGAGGCAAAGACCUGGUCACGGCGUCUCUGGCUCACCAGGUGGAGGGAACGGCAAAACUCACGCUGGCCCAAGAGGAGGAACAGAGAAGCUUCCUGGCUGAGGCCCAGCCGACUGCUGACCCGGAAAAGUUUCUCGAGGCUUUUCAUGAGGUCCUGGAGAGGCAGAGGCUGAUGCAGUGUGACCUGGAGGAAGAGGAGAAUGUCAGAGCCACCGAGGCUGUGGUUGCACUCUGCCAGGAGCUGUACUUCAGCACCGUGGACACUUUCCAGAAGUUCGUGGAUGCCCUGUUCCUUCAGACGCUCCCUGGCAUGACUGGCCUCCCCCCGGAAGAGUGUGACUACUUGAGGCAGGAAGUCCAGGAGAACGCUGCCUGGCAGCUGGGGAAGUCAAAUCGCUUCCGGAGGCAGCAGUGGAAACUCUUCCAGGAGCUCCUAGAGCAAGACCAGCAGGUGUGGAUGGAGGAGUGUGCGCUGUCCAGCGUGCUGCAGACACACCUGCGGGAGGACCACGAGGGCACCAUCCGCGGCGUCUUGGGCCGACUGGGCGGCCUCACUGAAGAGUCCACGCGGUGUGUCCUGCAGGGGCAUGACCUGCUGUUGCGCUCAGCCCUCCGGAGGCUGGCACUCCGCGGCAACGCCCUGGCCACCCUGACGCAGAUGCGGCUAUCGGGGAAGAAGCACCUCCUGCAGGAGCUGCGGGAACAGCGUGCACUGGAGCAGGGGUCCUCCCAGUGCCUGGACGAGCAUCAGUGGCAGCUGCUCAGGGCCCUGGAGGCGCGUGUGCUGGAGGAGGCCAGCCGGCUAGAGGAGGAAGCACAGCAGACACGGCUGCAGCUCCAGCAGCGGCUCCUGGCCGAGGCCCAGGAGGUGGGGCAGCUUCUGCAGCAGCACAUGGAGUGCGCCAUUGGGCAGGCGCUGCUGGUGCAUGCACGGAAUGCAGCCACCAAGAGCCGGGCCAAGGACAGGGAUGACUUCAAGAGGACACUGAUGGAGGCGGCAGUGGAGAGCGUCUACGUGACCAGCGCUGGUGUCAGCCGCCUGGUGCAGGCGUAUUACCAGCAAAUCGGAAGGAUCAUGGAGGACCACGAGGAGAGAAAACUGCAGCACCUGAAGACCCUGCAGGGUGAGAGGAUGGAAAAUUACAAACUGCGGAAAAAGCAAGAACUCAGCAACCCUUCGUCGGGCAGCAGGACGGCAGGUGGCGCUCAUGAGACCUCCCAGGCGGUCCACCAGAGGAUGCUGUCCCAGCAGAAGAGGUUCCUGGCCCAGUUCCCAGUGCACCAGCAGAUGCGUCUGCACGCCCAGCAGCAGCAGGCAGGAGUCAUGGACCUUCUGGAAGCCCAGCUGGAGACCCAGCUACAGGAAGCUGAACAGAACUUCAUCUCCGAGCUGGCAGCCUUGGCCCGAGUGCCCCUUGCUGAAAGCAAACUGUUGCCUGCUAAGCGUGGGCUGCUAGAGAAGCCCCUAAGGACUAAAAGGAAGAAGCCCCUGCCCCAGGAAAGAGGGGACCUGGGGGUGCCCAACAAUGAGGACCUUGCCUCCGGGGACCAGACCUCAGGCUCACUCAGCAGCAAAAGGCUGAGUCAGCAAGAAAGUGAAGCUGGGGACAGUGGGAACUCAAAGAAGAUGCUAAAGAGAAGAAGCAACUUGUAGUUUAAGACCAGUCGGUGGGACAAGACCUGAAGCCCUGGGUCUGGGUGUGAAUUCCACCUUCCCUCCUGCAGUGCUGAGAGGCAGCGAGGACGGAGAGGACAGCGGCAUCUCUAGGCUCUUCUGAGAGGGACAGAGAAAGAAUAGAAAUGUGCCCUAAAAGCAUAAAUGAGUAUCACCUGAGAAAAUUAGGCAUUCCCGUCUUGGAAACACGUCUCUGUGAGUUUGCAUUUCAUUUGGCUUGGAGCCCUGGCUCGAUGCCUCAUGGAUCUUUCUCCCCAAGGAGGGACGUCUUGAGGGGUCCGAGCCUCAGGCCAAGGACCCCUGAUGCAGACUCUGGAAUCCCUGGCCCAAAGGCCUGUCUGGGCCCAUCUGGGGCUGAGGACACACAGAUACAUAAUGACACCUGCAGAAAUGUAUUCUCUGAGGACACUUAGAAUAUGAGGAAGAGGGUGUGGCCCAACCCUCACUUCACCUGGGGAGGGGCUUCUUCCGGACAGUAGACACCCUGCCCGUGCAGAGAGAUGUCAUGGGGGCACCUGCUCUCCCUGAUAGAUGCUGAGAGCAUCCAGAAACUUCCAGACCAGCCCUCUCACCACACCCAGAAGAGGCCUUUCCCAUCUGGAGAGAAGCUUCCAGACCAGCCCUUCACACACCACAGCCAGGAGGGGCCUUUCCCACCUGGAGAGAAACUUCCAGACCAGCCCCUCAUACCACAGCCAAGAGGGGCCUUUCUCACCUGGAGAGAAAUUUCCAGACCAUCCCCUCUCACCACAGCCAGGAGAGGCCUUUCCCACCGGUAGAGAAACUUCCAGACCAGCCCCUCACACCACAGCCAAGAGAAGCCUUUCCAGCCUGGAGAGAAACUUCCAGACCAGCCCUCUCACUACAGCCAGGAGAGGCCUUUCCCGCCUGGAAACUUCCGGACAAGCCUCUCACACACCACAGCCAGGAGAGGCCUUUCCCACCUGGACAGAAACUUCCAGACCAGCCCCUCUCACCACAGCCAGGAGAGGCCUUUACCACCUGGAGAGAAGCUUCCAGACCAGCCCCUCACACCACAGCCAGGAGAGGCCUUUCCCACCUGGAGAGAAACUUCCAGACCAGCCCCUCAUACCACAGCCAAGAGGGGCCUUUCUCACCUGGAGAGAAACUUCCAGACCAGCCCCUCACACCACCGCCAGGAGAGGCCUUUCCCACCGGGAGAGAAACUUCCAGACCAGCCCCUCACACCACAGCCAGGAGAGGCCUUUCCCACCGGGAGAGAAACUUCCAGACCAGCCCUCUCACUACAGCCAGAAGAGGCCUUUCCCACCGGGAGAGGAACUUCCAGACCAGCCCCUCACACCACAGCCAGGAGAGGCCUUUCCCGCCUGGAGAGAAGCUUCAGGCCAGCUCCUCACACCACAGCCAGGAGAGACCUUUUCUGCCUGGAGAGAAACUUUCAGACCAGCCCCACACACCACAGCCAGGAGAGGCCGUUCCUGCCUGGAGAGAAGCUUCCAGACCAGCCCUUCACACCACAGCCAGGAGAGGCCUUUCCCACCUGGAGAGAAACUUCCAGACCAGCCCCUCUCACCACAGCCAGGAGAGGCCGUUCCCACCUGGAGGGAAAAUUGCUCCUUUGAUGGAGGUUAGGGACUGUCACCCUCAGCACUGUGAACAUACCGGGCGAGAUCAUUCUUCAGGGGAAGGAGCUGCCCAGAGCAUCACAGGAUGUUCCAGUGUCCCUGGUCUCUGCCCACCAGAUGCCAGCACUCCCACCAUUCGUGGCAACCAAGGAUGUCUCCAGACACUGCCCCGUGUCCAUGGGGUUAUCACCCACUGUGCUGAGUCAAAGGGUGCCUUGCCCUGGUCUAAUCCAGGACAUAGCCGUGGAUACGUCCAAAAAUCCCCAGAACCUAGUGAGCCCUCUGGCUCUGGGAGCCCCUAUCUCAGGAAUUUUCAGGGUCAUUUGUGACUUUUCAUUUCUUAAAACCUGAAAUAGACUCUCUUAGAAACAAGUGACUCCUUCCCAGUGGCCAAAACUUAAUCAUCAGAGCGCUUCCUUCAGUUCCUCACCCAUCAGCCAGUGGGCUCUCCAAAGUUAACCAACAGCUCCCUCUUGUGGUUCACUAAAAAACUUGGUUAUUCCAUGGAGUUGUGCAAAGCUAUGGCUUCCUUGGUGCAAUAUUCUUAAAACCUGCUUUGCAUAGAAAUCACUUUUGCCCAGGCUGGAGUGCAGUGGCGUGAUCUCGGCUCAUGGCAAUCUCCAUCUCCCGGGUUCAAGCGAUUUUCCUGCCUCAGCCUCCCCAGUAGCUGGGACUACAGACGUGUGCCACCACGCCUGGCUAAAUCUUUUUUGUAUUUUAUUUUAGUAGAGACGGGGUUUCACCAUACUGGCCAGGCUGCUCUCGAACUCCUGACCUCAUCGUCCACCUGCCUCGGCCUCCCCAAAGUGCUGAGAUUAGGCGUUAGCCACCGCGCCCGGCCAGAAAUCACUUUUAUAUUGUCACAUGGGCCCUCUGCACAGAGUCCGAUGGCUCCUCCCGGGGAAGCCUGAUUUUGUGACGUGUGUAUAGUAAAUGCAGGCCCUCUGGCAGCACCAUAAUUGGUCGGUUACCCUGAGCCCAGAGCUCUGAAAGCAUCUGUGGAAUGAUCACGGGACCCUUCUCCUCUGAGAAGGCUCCCGGCUGCCUCCCCGCCACCGAGCUUGUAGCCUGAAUGCCUGGCUGUCGCAUGGAGCAUUUUGCUUCUGGGGUGUCUUCCUUAGCCAAAGGGAACGUGUCAUUUGCUCGACCCUGGCCCACCCUUGCCGCCCAGCUGUUGUGCUGGGCACAGUCUGGGGCACAGGCCUCCAUGAUGAAGACGCGUGGGCUGUCGGUGCUUUCAUCCGUCACAAACUGGCACCUGUACCUGCCAGCAGGAGCAUGAUGGGGACUUCCAUGCUGGAAUUGCUCCCUGAUUAAAAUGAGAUAUGGCUAUUUGGAAGACACUGCAUUUUAGCCAGUGUACCUGGGCACAGACUCGGGGCUGCCCUGAAGCUGAUGAAGGCUUGAAGGACGGAAGGGCUGAGCCACAUGAAGGCAGCACUCAGGGCCAGGGGAGAGAGAAGAGGAUCAGCAGUGCAGCCCCAGGAUGCCUCGCAGACGUGCCUUCUGCCAUGAUUGUGAAGUUCUAGCCACGUGGAACUGUGAGUCCAUUAAACCUCUUUUUCUUUAUAAAUUACCCAGUCUUGGGUAUGUCUUUAUCAGCAGAGUGAGAACAGACUAAUACACCAACAAAUGCAGAGGGGCCAGAACCACCCCUUCCUGGGACAUCAGAGCCAACAGUUAAGUGGUCUGGAUUCCAAACUCAUUUACUUAAUGUCGAUAGGUUGAAAUUGGCCAUGGCAAGAGACUUAUGUUGAAACUUAAUACCCAAUGUGGCAGUACUGAAAGGUGGGGCCUGUUAGAGGUGAUUGGGUCAUGAGGGCUCUCCCUUCAUGAAUGGAUUAAUUCAUUCAUAGAUUAAUGUAUCAGUGAGUCAGUGGAUUAAUGGGUUAUCAUGGGAGCGGGACCAGCAGCUUUAUAAGCAGAGGAAGCGAGACCUGAGCCAAUACACUCAGCCCCCUCACCAUGUGAUGCCCUGCACUGCCUUAGGACUCUGCAGAGUCCCCACCAGCAAGAAGGCUCUCACCAAAUGCACCAGCACCACCCCAACCUUGGACUUCUCAGUCUCAAAGUCUGUAAGAAAUGAAUUCCUUUUCUUUAUAAAUUACCCCAUCUCAGGUAUUCAGUUACAGUGAUGCCAAAUGGACUAAGACAGAAAAUCGGUAACAGAAGUGGGGUCCACAGAACUAGCAAACACUACAAACAAGGGCUUUCUACCCCACCCACCUUCACCCAUUGUUCAACAUUGAUUUGGCAGCACACUUCUGGACCACUGAAUCAGAAGGGUCAAUCACCUGACUUACAACAAAGGCCCCACUGCAUCUUAAUGGGGGAAAGAAUAGUCUUUGCAAUAAAUGGUGUUGGGUCAAUGGGAGAUCAUAUGGGAAAUGGAGAACCUUCAGUCCUACCUUAUAUUGUACAUAAAGAUUAUUGAGAGAUGGCUCAGAGACCUAAAUGUGAAAGAUAAAACUUCUAGAAAAAACCCAGAAGACUACUGUGGUAGGCAGAAUAACGCUCCCCGUCCCUGCCAACAAGAUGACCACAUCCUAAUCCCUGGGCCUGUGAGUAUGUUAUGUCACAUGGCUGGGAGAAUUGGGUUGCAGAUGAAUGAAUGAGAAUAGCCUUCCCCUAAAACUUUCUGAGAAACUCUCUCUCCCUCCUCCCAAAAUCUCAAGAGGUAAAAGGAAGUCACAUGCCUUAAAAGGAGUGUUGCAGCUCAGUCUCCAAGAACUAAGGAUUAUCUGAGCUACCAGGUCUCCUGUCCCCUGUAACUGUGCCUCUUGGAGGCGCUGGGGAACCCAAAGUUCGACAUGGGCUCUAGAUUAUGCUGGUUGGACAGUGGCUCCCAUGACCUGGGAGUCAGGCAAGCACCCCGUCAGAGUCUGUCUUAGAGAAGGUGCUAGGGCUGCUUCUGCUUCCACUUCCACCCUGACAGGACUGAGGAGGCCAGGCCCAGAGAACAGGCUGGAUAACUUCAUCCUGCCAACUUUACUUUUCUGGAAGUUUCCCUUUAAUAGUCCAAAUGGGCCAAAGCCGAACAUCAAAAAUCCUUACCAUCCGUUCUUGGUCUUUCCAUCCAAAAAUCCUUACCAUCCAUUCUUGGUCUUUCUCAGUAGUUAGUUAACCUUGUUUCAAGGAAGUCUAUAACUGACCCUGAGCCAACACUUCUUUCAACCUUGACAAAGGUAUCCACACGAAGCCGAGGAGCGGGGGAGGAGAAGGGUACAUGAAAAGCCCUGCGUUGAUGUGGGACCAGAGCAUCCAAAGCCAUCUGCCUCAAAUGCCCUUGGAGCUCAGUAAUUAGGAGCAAGGAGCUUUGGACUAGGGCCCAAAGUGCCUGGGUCCUGGAUUCAAAUCCUGGUUCCAUCACUUCCUAAGUGUGUGAUCCUAAACAAGUUAUUGAUCUCACUCUGAGUCAGUUUCCUCAUCUGUACAAUGGGGAUAAUAAUCCCUACCUCAUAGAGCACCUGGCAUAUAGCAACUGCUAUACAGCUAUCAGCCCAUGUAUUUGUUGUCAUUACCAGCAACUUCAUCACUAUCACCAACACCACCAUCAUCAUCACCACUAUCGUCACCAUCAUCACCAUCACCACCAUCAUUACUGUCACCACCAUCAUUGUCAUCACUAUUACUAACAACAGCUAAUGGAAGCAAGCAACUUUGCCUGCUGUUUUUAUCCGUCCUUUAGUGUAUCUCUAGCUCAUGGAAAUGGAAGGAAGAAAUGUGAAGUUUAGGAGAUUGGAGCUUCCAGUCUGAGGCUGAUCCAUACAAUACAAGAAGAAAGAGAGCCAGGAAAGGCCCAACAGGAGGGAAUCAAUGCAAGAUUUGAGCCUAUUUUGUGGAAGCCCGCCCAUCAGCCGUCUUCCCUCUCUUCGCCUCCUUGGGUCUCAGGAACUCAGCCUUCAGAAGUCAUGAACUGAAUCUCUCCUCCCACCCCCACAUCCACCAGUCUCUACCAAGAGUGAGUCCUCAGGAAGCAGCCACCACCAUUCGUUAUCACGCGGGGGGACUGCCAAGCAUUCGUACCCAAUCCAGACACCACCACUGAAAUGAAAGUGCCCUAGUCAGGUCAGUGGGCAGUUCAUUUUCUUUAUUUUUUCACAAGCUUUGAAUUCAGAAAUAAGAGCCACAACAAGUUGGUUGUUAAGUAAAAAUGGGAGUGAUUACAAAGGAAAACUUUGUACAAAACUUUAAAAAUCUGACUGCCCCGUCAACUGCCUCAGAGGGACCAGGACUCAGGCCACGCAGGGGCAGCCAUCAGCCCCCCAUCGUCAGCCCCGAAUGGGGAUGGGGAGACCUCUUUCUGAGUGUGAACCUGGCUCGGCCUGAAGCCUAGAGCUGGCUUGAAGAACACACACAGACCAGAAGACAGCACGGUGAGUUACAAGUGCCACGGAGACCAGGGUUUCUGACACAGGAUGUGGAGGAUGCUUCUCUGCAACCUAGUGCAAGGCUUCCCCUGCCAUUCCGAGAAUUCACGGAUCUCACAGGUGGAGGUGGGGCGAGCUUCUUUCUAGUGUGGACCAGAGGUGGGGGCAAUGAGUAAACAUCUUCACUGUAAGGGUUUUGGGACUGCCCCUCAGGGCUUGAGGUCUCGGCAUCGUGUCUCAGUCAGUCCUUGGCGAUGUCCCCUCAGACGCACUCACAGACUUGCAUACGUAAUUUAGUAACAUGCAUCAACUAUCCUAGAACAUCUACAGGGUGCAAAGGAACCACCACUCAGAGAAUCAUGGAGCCAGUGGAGUUAGAAGUGGAAGGGACAGAACAAGACAAUGCUAAAACCUGUGGUUCACUAGGAAGGGGGAAUGAAAACACCAUGCUCCGAGGUGGAUUCAGCAUGAACACAACUGUGGGGCAAGGAAUUUCCAAGCAAACACACCACACUAGUACCACUUCUUCCUAAACAGAAAAGGGAAAGAGCAUCCUUCGACUUCCCCCUCCCUCCAUCAGCACCAACUAAAACUGUGGGUUUCAAAAACACUGACAGGAAAAGGGAUGGACAUGAUUCCCAGAAUCCUUCAGGCUAGCUCCUCCGCGCAUCCACGUUCAACCGAGGCUGGUGAUGUUGGAGCGGCCACCAGGGGGCGCCACGAUGCGGUGGCCGGUGCGCCUGGGAUUGUUGUCAUCUAUCUGGGCACCUGAAAGAGAGCGCCAAUCGCUGCUGGAUGGGAUCUGUUAGCAUCAGUUCCACGCUGCUCCUGGAGGCCAUGUACUCUGCCAUGCACUCCACUGGACCCACCUUCAUUCAGGGCUCAGUCCAGGACCAGCCAUGGGAAGCCUCCCUGGCCUCCACAGAGUCCACUGCUCCCUCUUCUGUGCCCCUCAGUCCCUGGGCUCCCCCCACCUUCAGCCCUGACCACCUUGUGGUGUUCUUGUCAAAAUCCCCAGUAAAAUCCGACAUUCCUGAGACAGGUGAUCAAACACUUACUGAGUGCCUACUGUGUGCAGGCGCACAUUUGGUGCUUUAACAUGUUACUGCAUUUAGGGCACACAAUCAUACUAUGAAGGGGGUGUUUGUACUCCCAACUUACGGGUGAGCAAUUUGAGGUUCAGGCCACGUGUCUUGCGGGACACAGGUGUUGGGUGGGGAAGCCAGGAUUGAAGCCCAAACUGGUUGGUUUUCAAAGCCCAUGAUCUUAGGCACACUGUCCCACACUCCAAAGGUAUUUUACAUAUUGUGUGUGUACACAUUUGUAUAUGCAUGUGCAUAUGUGUGUGCAUGUGCAUGUGAACUCCGCAAGCUGGAUUUACUUCCCUCAUUGGCGAUAGGUGGAUCUGAAGGGGGGGGGGGUGGUGUGCAGAGGUUCUUAAUUUUAAUCUUUCAAAACCAACCAUCCAUUCUACUUUUACCUAUUCUCUUGCAUAAAGAUGUAAAAUUCUAGCAGCAAACCCAGUGCCUGGAGCUCAACAAAUAUUUAUUAAAUGAGUAAAUCAUGAAGGGUGGAUAAUGCUGAAAGGUGGGAAGGAUAGAGUCCUUAUCAGGGAGGGGAAGUUGAGCCGGCGGAACUGAGGAAAAUCAAAAAGAGAAAGCAAAUAAGCUGUAAGUCUGCCUUUCUUCAUGGUCUACAACACAGCCUUCCUGUACUCAACUUAUCACCAGAUCCUCAGCUAACAGAAAAACGUAAGUAAGUUAGCUCACUGCAACCACAGCAUUAUCAGUACUGCACAAAGCCCUCUUCGGCACACAGCACAAGCACCAUCCUAUAAAAUCUCCAGCAAGCCUUUGUUUCCUUGCAGUCGGCUCCUUUCUUGCUGACCUACCCACUGUACCCUUUCAUACUUUUUCUAAUACAUCUGACUUUCUUUACCGACAACUGUCUUGGUGAAUUUUUUUUACUAGCUGCAGAACACUGGCCCCAGGUAGUUGUCACCUGCAACAGGAAGGAGACUCAAGUUUCAGUGCUAAUCAUGCCUUGAAUUUGGGCAAUUUGGAGUAAGACACCACCCCACUCCCUUGGCCUCAUUUCCUUUUCUGCACAAUAAGAACAGUAGACUAGAUGAGCCCCUUCCAACUCCAACAUUACAUGAUUUGUCUAUGUAAGCCACUAAGAAUUUGGUUCACAGUAGUGACUUUUCUUUUCUCCCAUUGUUUCACUGGUAGACAAUAUGUCUUCUUGCAAUACAAGUCUCCCCUAAAGGCCUGGAAUCAGGCCUAGCACUUAGUAACUUUUUCCUUACAACCAUCUGUACCUUGCUGGUUGCAUGUCUGUACUUUGAAAAUACCUGCUGGAAAAAAGGACACUAAUAUGGUUUGGACUUUUGUCCCCCAAAACUUCGUGUUGAAAUUUGAUCCCAAAGUUGGAGGUGGGGCCUAAUGGGAGGGGUUUGGGUCAUGAAGGACAGACCACUCAUGAAUGGCUUGGUGUCAGCCUUACAGUAAUGAGUAAAUUCUUGCUCUAUUAGCUCUCGGAAGAACUGGUUGUUAAAGAGCACCUCUGCCUUCUUCCUCUGUUGCCAUGUGAUCUCUGCACACGCUAGCUCUCCUUCGCCUUCUGCCAUGCUGGAAGUAGCCUGAGGCCCUCACCAGAAGCAGACGCUGGCACCGUGCUGCUUGUACAGCCUGCAGAGCCGUGAGCCAAGUAAACCUCUUUAAUUACCCAGCCUCAGGUAAUCCUUUAUAGCAAUGUAAAUGGACGAAAACAGACACUAACUCAUGGUACAGCUCUAUAACGUAACAUACGCAGAUAUUAAAAAGGGCAUCUGUGAGGUUGUUAUGAUGUUGGAAAGCAUCUGUGUUGUUGGUACCAAAUGAAGUCACCUAUCAACCUGCCAAGAGGCUGGCUGACAGCAGUGGUGCUGUGGGCCUCAGGAGGACUAAGAGUGAAACUGAGAGAACAAGGGUGAGGAGGGGCCCUUCCAGGUGGCUUUUAACUUCAUUGUUAUUCUUGUUCUAAGAACAACGGGGAGGAGGAUUUUCUGUCCAUGUUUAAUUGCAAUUGUGCAGUGUUUAAUUGCAUAACUCCAGAACAGUGGUCCAGUUUGCAAACUCCUUGAGAGCUUGUGUCUUGUUGCACCCAGAUAGCUUUUUCCCAGGAUGAAGCCAAUCCCUGGUUUGCUGAUUGAGCAUCACAUGACUUUUAGCAUUCUAUUUAGGGUCCAUUUUGUGCAAAAAUAUGAAACACUGGAAGCUCUUCCAUCAAAGUCUUAUGGAGAGUGAGAUGAAUGGGGAGGCCUCCUUGAUUCAUGCCUCCUCGGCAUAAUCACUGAAUCAGACACUUCCUGAAUGGAUAAGAGGUUCUGCCACCACACAAUCUGAAUUCACACGUCAUCCUCUCUCUCUCUCUCUCUUUGCCCCUUCCACUCUCUCUUUUGCUAAGCAUAUCGCCUUUCCUGACCAGGAAUUAGCAAACGGGUCCAUUGACCAAAUCCGGCCCACCGCCUGUUUCUGUACGAUCCAUGACCUGAGAAUAGUUUGUACAUUUUCAAAUGGCUAUUGAAUAUAACAUCCUAGAUGUUGACAUCCUAGAUGUUGCCUCUUAGCUUACAAAGCCUAAAGUAUUUACUAUCCGGCCUUCUAAGAAAAAAAAUCACCAUACUCUUAGUACCCAGCACGGUGUGCAACCCAUGCAACGCCUCAAAGAGUUUGCAGGACAAAAUUCCAGUUCAACUUUCUCAACGUGUGCGUGCCUGCCCUCAUGUGGCCAUCUCACCAAAUCACAGAUACACUGCCCUGAGACCUUAAGAAAGUCAGGAGGGAUCAGGUCAACAUCUAAUUUUGUUCCCACACAUUUGUUGAGCACCAAGUCCUGGUAUUUUGACACUGGAUUUCUUGGGGCUUCCGUUUCCUCUUUAAAUAAAUAGGGUAUAAUGUUACUUUAUGGAGUAGUGAGGAUAAAAUAAAAUCAUGGGUUAUGAAAGUGCUUAGUACACUGCAGUGGGUGAACAGGCUAAAGACUUACACAGAGCACAUGCCCUGCAAAUGGCAGCUACUCCCAUCUCUUGUUCAUCCCCACCACUCCAUGUUUACUUUCAUGAGGAAGAGUGUGAAAGUGUCCCCAAAUGUGUGUAAGGAUGAGCACUGGGACAAUUUUGGUACCUCUCUUUGUAAACCCACAUCAGGUACCACCAUGUUGCCCCCCUAACAUGGACCCCCCUCUGCUUGGUGACCAUGCCAGCCCACUCUGCCCCACCAGUGAGAGCAGGCUCGGGUGGGGCACACUCCCUUCCCUGCUUCUUCAUCUAGUGUCCAAGGCCACGUGUCCAUUUCCUCAGAAGCAGCAGGAAGGACUCGGCCUGAACUGCUGCAAUUGUGGGGAGCCUGGGCCACCACUCUUUCCUACCUGAUAAGCUGAAGUUGGACUGGUGGAGGUUUCUGAUGGGUGGGGGCUGGUGUUUAGAAGGCGAAGAUUUGGCUGAAGGAGCGGGAGUUGCAUAUUUGGGUGUAGCUGGUACCUCGUACACAGGACCGUCAUACAUGCCCCUGGAAACCCCUUGCAAUCCAAAAACCUAAACAGAGGAAGGGAGAGUGUGAUUGAUCGACACUGUGCAUGUGUGCCCUUCUGGGCAGAUAAAGCAGAGCCCUGCGGGCGAGAGAGAAACCUGAGGUCACUUCAAAUGUGCAUGCACACACACACACAACACGCACACACGACAGGUGCACUUCACACACAUGCAGCCGCACACAGGCAUUCAUACACACAAGCAUGCAUACACACACAUCUACAUACCCACAUGCAUACACAUACAGACGCACACACCACGCACACGCACUCACAUACAUGCAGUCAUGCACACAUAUAUGCAUGCACAUGCAGUAACAAAACAGGCCUACACAGUAGCAUACACGCGUGAACACGCACACACACUUAAAUCACAUACAGAUCUUCACAAAGGCAUACUCACAUAUGUAUACACAUGCAUACAUGCCCACACACACACUCAUACAGGUAUACACACCCAUAUAUACACUUACACACACGCAUACUCAUACACACAAAGCUUCAUGCAGGAGGACCCCAAAUCCCUUCCAAAGAGAAGUCACUUUGCCUGACACUACCACCUACCCACCCCCGGAAAGGACCCCUGAGUCCCAGACAAGGCAGCAGCAACGGGCCCAUCUUCAUGUAUGUUCUUGUAGAAGUCAACAGCGAGGCAAAGAUUCGGGGGGCAGAUAGUUUGUUGGGAGAUGGUUCCAGAAAGGGGGAAGGAGUGGGGAGCUGAGACAGGGAGGGAGAAAACUCAGUACAGAGGGACAAGGAGUGGGCCAGGUCUAUGGGGGGCAGGGCUGGGGAUGCUGUGGGGAGGACACCUCCACACCAGCCUGCAGGAGGACGAGGAAGGAGGGCAAUGGAGCCACAGCCCUAGCCCCACUGGGAAAGGGUUGUGGGGGCAGAGACCCUGAAAGCAGCAGGGCUUCCAGGCAGGAGGCUGUCAGCCUGCUGGGAACUGCUGACAGCAGCCCAGGUGACCUCAGGGAUGGCCAAGGUUGGGAGGGCACCUGCUCCAGGCACUGGAGAACAGCAUGUGUUCAGGGACCUGUACAGGGUCCCAGCAUGAGUCAGUGGCAGUGCCCUAACCCAACACGGGGCUUCAUCCUCCAUAUCAGGUGACAGUGCCCUGACCCCAGGCCUGGCUCCCUCCUUCUCUGCAGGUGAUAGCACCCUGACCCCCAGCUCUGGGCUCCUGUCUCUCCAUAGGAGGAAGCCUUAAUUUUAGCACCAAGUUUAAAGACCCAGCACCUGCACAUCAUGUCAACGGCCCUCCCCUCUGUCCCUGGAGCCCUGCUCCCCGACUCCCUGGGCCUCACUGUAUCCUGUGCAUUCUCUGUGGCUGUGGCAUUGCUUCCUGGGUGAGGCCGUUCAUCACUCCCUGAAGCUCAGGUGGCCAGAGGCAGGCUCUGAUGCAGGUCUCUCCUUCACCUGGUCUAGCUCCUGCAGGCAUGAAGGAAUCCCUGUGCAAUGGGACCCCCCGAUCCUAUUGCUCCUGCAAAUUGCUGUCUUGGCAUUUGGGGUCAGAUAUCUGCCCUCACGGAAGCUGACUGUUAACCGCAGGCCUCAGCUUCAGACCAAGAAGGAAAUGAAGCCAGCCAAGGGGUGUGUCUGCCUCUUCAGUGGGUGUCCCAGCCAGGGAUUUCCAUGAGUCCCCUUGUCCUCAUAUGGCCUGCUGCCUGUGCCUGGCCUUGUCUCGGAUCUGACUUGUUUCCACCCCAUCCCUUGUUUCCCCAUCCAGUGCAAAGCAUCUGUGCGACUUGGUGUCUUUGACCUGGUGCUACACCUUAUGGAAGCUGGGGAGAGACCAAAACCAGAUGCAGAGCCUCCCAGUCCGGGCUGGAGCCUGGGAAUGCAGGAAGAUGUCCUGAGGUCAGUGCUAAGGUUGUUCAAGGAAAAUAAGGAACGACAGGGCAGAAACGUCAAGGGAGGAAGGAAAGGAAGAAAGGGCGGAUCUGAAGGAAGCCCUGCCUGCAAGAUGCCAGGGGUAACACCUUGCUCCACAGGGCCAGACCCGAGGGUUUCUGAGCCGUGACUCUGGCUAAGCCCUUCACUGCUCUGGGCUGCAAAAGGAGGAUCACAGCACCUCCCGUGGGUGGGCAGGAUUACUUAAGAUGACGCAGGACAGCGCCCAGAGCAGCUUGGUGCUCCGGGAACGCCUUCCGCGGAAUGAAGCGGCCCAUGCCCUUGUUGACGUUGAUGUUUCCGUCUUCAAAGACGAUCUUGCCCUGGCUGAUGACCACUAGUGGGGAGCCGUGGCACUCCAUACCCUCGAAGAUGUUGUACUCCACCGCCUGCACCAACAGCCUCAGUGUUACUUCCCAGGAUUUGCUCUGCCCCAAACGAGCUGUUCAUAACAGCGAUUUUGCCUAACAUUAUAUCAUAAGCGUGUUCCAAUGUUUUUUUUUCUCUCUAAAAAUACCUUUUAUUGACUGUAAUAUUCCACUGUAUGGUCCACAGUGUAUAUAACCAACAACUCACCGUUGCGCAUGUAGGCUGCCGGUGGCUUUCUAUAAUCAAAUCAAUAUUGUUCUGGGGCAUCACAAAGAGGAAGGGGGUCCCCCGGGGUUAUGCAAUGUGGCUGCUUUGACUGUACUGGACAUAAAAAUAAGUAAAAUGUUCUUCAUUUUACUUAAAAUGUGUCUUUAAAUAAAAUUUUUUUCUCUAGGUUUCUAAAAUCAAA